ACCCUAGCGAAAAUAACUUUUUUGGUAAGUUUCUUAGAAUUCCAUCAUGGAUAAGUCAGUUAUUGUGCUUCCAUGCAUGUUGUACAUUCCAAUAUACACUGUAAUUUUUCACAAAAAGGACGAUUUUACGUUUUUUAUCAUGGACACUCUUCCACAUACCCAGACCCCUCUAGGAAACCCUUAUUCACUUAGGUUUGUGCCCUUCCGUAAUUUUUUAAAGAUCCUGUAAUUCUGUACACAGACAUAGAUACAUCCACACAUAUAGACAAUGCCUUUUUCAGUUCUGAUUUUUCAAAAAUGGAAUUAUAUACUUCGUUGCAUUUAAUUAUUAAAUAAAUAAUGGCUCAUGUGAAUGUUUCCAUGAGAAUCUUAUAGUAACUGUAUCACAGUUUAUUCAUUAAUUCUCUACUGAUGAACGUUUACUUUUUUGUGAGAUCUUGACCAUCAGGAACAGUAUUGCAUUGCACGUCCCUGUAUUUUAAGUUCACAUAUACUGGUACUUUUAUUUCAGUGGGCUGGAUUUCCAGGGAUCUUAAUGGAUAAGGAAUAGAUUUGACCAGGAAUGUGUUCAAUUACUGUUAUAUGAAGAAUCUUGAAGCAAAAAACAUUAAAUAUGAGGAAGUUAUUUUCUAAAGACAGGGUUUCAUUCCUGUUGUCCCAGCUGGAGUGCAAUGGCAACUCGGCUCACUGCAGCCUCCACCUUUGGGCUCAAGCAGUUCUCCUGCCCUAGCCUCCAAGUAUCUGGGAUGAGGGUAAUUUUAAGUACAGGUUGAGCUUCCCUAAUCUAAGAACCCUAAAUUAGAAAUGCUCCAAAAUCUUAAAGUUUUUGAACACCGACAUUAUGCCACAAGGGGAAAACGUACCUGAGCUUAUGUAACAGGUCACACAGCUGGGUAUGGUGGUAUUCCUGCAAUCCUAGCACUUUGGGAGGCGGAGGCAGACAGAUCGCUUGAGCUCAGGAGUUUGAGACCAGCCUGGGGAAUAUGACGAAAAACAUUUCUAUCAAAAAUUCAAAAAUUAGCCAGGCAGUGGCACACCUGUAGUUCCAGCUACUUGGGAGGCUGAGGUGGGAGGAUUGCUUGAGCCUGAGAGGUUGAGGCUGGAGUGAGCCAAGAUGGCACCACUGCACUCCAGCCUGGGUGACAAAGUGAGAGACCUUCCAAAAAAAAAAAAGAAAAAUGCAGGCGCAACACAGUUUAUUCAGUGUCCCCAAGGGAAAAAACAACCUGCGCCCUUCAACUGUAAUGUAUCUUUUCUGCACGUGCAUACUCAGAUUCCCACACAAGCACGCCCUCCGAGGGUAAUAAGACAGCUCAGUGUGCACAACCUUUGUUUCAUGCACAAAGUUAUUUAAAAACAUUAUAUAAAAUUACUUUCAGGCUAAGUGUAGAGUUUACAUGAAACAUAAAUGAAUUUUAUGUUUAGACUUGGGUCUCAUACUGAAGAUAUCCCAUUAAUGUGUAUGCAGAUAUUCCAGAAUUUGAAAAAAUCUGAAACACUUCUGAUCCCAAGCAUUUUGGAUAAAGGAUACUCAGCCUGUACUAAUUUAUCUUAAUGAAAUCUAGGAACUAAGAUGAGGAGAGAUAGAAGAGGGAGAUAAAACAUCUUAAAGGUCUAAUGGAGGAAGAGGAAAAACAAGAACAGAGGAAAUAAACUAACCAACCUAAAGGGCUCAUCCUUUAGGUGGAUAACUAGGGAGAAUUGGAGCACGGGAAAUUCAGUGUGGAAACUUUUUCAUGUCGUAUGUCUAGAAAAGGCACAGCUAUCAGAAUGAAUUUAGAACUUCUAAGUAAGUGUGGAAAACAGAAUAAAAACAAACUUGGUAGCACAAAUAGGGAAAAGAAAGGGGAGAUUAAAUGAUAAAUAUAGAAGGAAUAAAAUUAAAUGUGAAUAAUUUGAGUUCACUCUUAGACAUAAAAAUGCUGUUUACAAGCACUUUUUAAUUUAAAGAGUGAAAAAUGAAAUUUAAUAUUUAUGUAAAAUUAGAAAAAAAAGUUCAAAUUAAUGAAGCAGAAAUAAAUAGAAUUAAAAAUAAAUGAAUUCUUUGAAAAAGAGUAAAUUCAUAAGUAAGUUUAACUUGCACAUCUGACCAAGUGAAAAAAGAGAGAGCAGAAGUAGGCAAAAUCAGGAAUAAGGAGACAACCAUGGAUCUAGGGGGGAGGAACUAAGUUUGCUGCUCUGUAGCACCAAAUUUGAAAACAACAAGAAAUGGUGGAUUUCCAUUUAAAAUACAAACUACUGAAAUUGAAUCAAGAAAAGUCUGAAUGGUUACAAGUUCUAUUGUUAAAACUGUUAUAGGCCAUAAAUAAAAGCUUCCAAAUUUAUUUUACAAAGUAAUAUCAAAACCUAACAAAUAGUGUUUAAAAAGAAAACUGUAGGCCAAUUUCACAUGUGACAGAAUAUAUAUGCAAAAGUUUAAAUAAAAUAUUAGGAAAUAGAAUCCAGCAAUAUAUGCGAAAAAUCCUUAUAACAAAACAGAUGGUAUUGCAGGAAUUCAGUGCUGGUUCUGUACCUGAAAAUGUCUAUAUACUAUAUUAAAUUGAAAAGCUCAUUUGAAAAAAAAAAACCUGUAUUCAGUAGAUGCUACAAAUGGCCUUCGAUAAAAUCACCAUUCCCAGUAAAAACUCUGUAAAAUGGGAAUAGAGGGAAAUUAUCUAAAUGUAAUAAGGACUAAGUUUUAGAAAGUAAUAGGACAUAAUUUUAAAUGAUAAAAUCACAAAAAUCUCCAUUGUAAACAGGUUACAGAUAGGCAUCCCUGUUAGUACUAUUUUUAUUUAACAUAGUGUUAGUAGUUUAAGACAAAGUAAAAUGUUGAAGAAUAGAUUAAAAUAACUGUGCAAAAGAUAGUAAAAGGAGGAUUUGCCUUUUCGCAUUUUAGAUUAUAGCAAUAUGUAAACAUUUAAGGAACAGAAAAGUAUAUUAGUAGAACAAGUAGAGAGUGAAAAAAUUCUGGUACAAAUUGGGAAAUUAGUAUAUAACAACAUAGUGUUAAAUUCAAUGGGAAAAGUUUAAUAAGAGGAUUUGGUAUCAACUGGCUGUCCAAAGAUAAAAAUGGACCGUCCUAUCACAUACAAAAUUGUUUUUUAGAUAAAGAUUUAAAUACAGGCACUCCUUCAUUUGCGUGGUGCACCUUGAGGUGUUGCAGAAAUGAUGAGAGCUGAAACUGCAAAGCAAUUUUAAUACUUUAUCUGUUGGAAAUCUUAUAGUUUUCCUGUGACCGUUAAAAUUUUCAUUAAACUAUUAAAAACACCCAUGACUGGUCACAAAUGUAUUGGGAAAUGGAAAAGAAUUAAUACACUAAAAAUACAAAAAAUAGAAAAUAUUUAAAAUUAUCUAAAAAUUUGAAACAUUAGAAAAAUUGAGAACUAGGCAGGGCGUGGUGGCUCACAUCUGUAAUUUUAGCCCUUUGGGAGGCUGAGGCAGGUGGAUCACCUGAGGUCAGGAGUUCGAGACCAGCCUGGCCAACGUGGGGAAACCCCGUCUCUACUGAAAAUACAAAAAUUAGCCGGGCAUGGUGGCACAAGCCUGUAAUCCUUGCUAACCAGGAGGCUGAGGCAGGAGAAUCACUUGAACCCAGGAGGUGGAGGUUGCAGUGAGCCGAGAUAGCACCACUGCACUCCAGCCUGGGCAGCAGAGUGAGACUCCGUCUCAAAAAAAAAAAAACAAAAAGAAAAAAAAAUUGAGAAUUAGGAUGUUUCUAUUUGUAAAAAGCUUAUCAAGAAUACUUUCAAUGAUGCUUGCCUUCUAAUUGUAUAACUUAAGAUAUGGAACAAGCAUCUCUUCUGUGCCUUGCCAAAUUGUCAUUUUCUUUUCUAAAUUUGUAUUAGUUUUCAACAUUUUAUAUAGUACUUUGCAUUUCCAAAGUCAUGAAGUAUUUCAGAGACUUCCUUUAAUGUGAUGUUUUUUUCCUCUGGGAUAUCUUCAUCUUUUGGUCAUAACCAGUUUCCAAUUCCACUUUCAGCAUUGCCACUUUUUGUUUCCUUGCUACACUUUCAUUUUUGUUGGUCAGUCCCCUCUUUUGACUGUUUACUUUUGUAAAAUGUCAAAUCAGUGUAUCACUGGGAGACAGGAAGGCAACACAGUUACACACUUUGCUGUUCAUGCAUAUACUGAAUAACAAAUAGGUGCCCAGUAACCAGUUGCUGUCAAAUUUUGGGAAAAGUUAUGUGAUUGCUUACUGAUCAUGAUGCACAUCUCUUAUUUACUUAGUGAUUUGUGGACCAAGCAUUCAGAAGCUAUGCACUUACUCAAAGUUGAUAUACUGUGGUAACUAAGUGUUGAACCAGGUUGUUGGGGACUGUUAUUUAUACUGUGAUGGCUGGUACCUGUGUAUUUCAGAACUGUGCAAAAGCAAAGACUGCUUGUGUUCAUGACACACACACAAAAUCUUGAAAGAUAAUCUGAGAGACUGCGUAUUUAGUCCUUCCUAAUGAAGACUUUCUAGUCUUUGUAUUAUUCCCAGAAAGCAUAAAAAGACGGACAUAUUUCAUAAUAUAAAAAUGAAUUUUUAUGGUAAAAAUAACAAAGCCAACAGGGAAAACAAUAGAUCCAGAAAAUUAUUUCUAAAACUGUUGAUGAACAAAAGGUAAAUUUCUGUAAUAUAUUAAAUUCUUGCAGUGUGACAAGAAAAGAGACCAUCAGUGUGAUAGAGCAACAGACAAAACAAAUCCAAAUGUCCAACAAAUGAGAAAGGAGGUCAGAUUCAUUAUUAGUUAAAGAAGUGCAAAUUAGAGAAACUGUAGAAUUUAAUAGGCUGUAUAUGACUUCUUGCUAGAGGUAAUACAGAGAAAGGCACUCUCAAACUUUGGUGGACAUGAGAAAACAACCUUUUGGGAAAGCAAUGUGGCCAGUAAAAUAAACCUGGCCAGUAAAUGUGUUAGUAAAAUAGCAUAUCUGUUUGCUAUAUUCUAGCAGUUGCUCUUCUGGAAAUCUAUCCCAUAGCAGAAAAUUUAGUAUUUCAUUUAAUUGCAGUAGGUUAGGUAGUACCAUAAAUGUUUUUGAAACCUGAGUACAAUUUGAGAAUAUCAGAUUUUUAACAUUUGGGUUUUUUUUUUUUUUUUUAAAGCAUUAAGUAAGGCUGGGCACAGUAGCUCACACCUGUAAUCCCAGCACUUUGGGAGGCCAAGGCGGGUGGAUUACCUGAGGUCGGGAGUUCGAGACCAGUCUGGCCAACAGGGUGAAACUCCGUCUCUACUAAAAAUAAAAAAAAAUUAGCUGAGCCUGGUGGCAGAUGCCUGUAAGCCUAGCUGCUUGGGAGGCUGAGGCAGGAGAAUUGCUUGAACCCCAGAGGCGGAGGUCAUGCCACUGCACUCCAGCCUGAGCAACAGAGUGAGACUCGCUGUUUCAAAAAAAAAAAAAAAAAAAAAAAGCAUUCAUUAGAGCCUGAGUUAGUUUCAAUUUUUUAUCUAAGAAGUAUCUGUUUUAGUUGAAAGAAGUACAUUCAUUUCUAGCUUUCAACAGUAGGUGUUUUCAGUCUUUGAUUCUGGGUUAUGAAGUUGCUACAGUUAAAGGGAUUUUCAGAUCAUUUCUAUUUUAAGAAUAUUUAUGUAUCUUAAGAACAGGUCUCUCUGAAAUGUAGUUAAUUUUUCCUGAAGAUAAAAGUAAUAUGAUUUGAAUCAUUGCUGUUUUAAGCAAUGUUUAAUAGAUACUGAUUGGUAUUUUCUUUUUCAUCAGUUUCAAAUUGAUUCUAUAAAUUUGAUAAGUUGGAGAGAAAAUUCAGAUAGCUAGAGAUCUGUGUAACAGAUGACACCAAUUAGCUUAAAAUUUAAAUCCUGACAUAACCAAGUCACCAUUGCAUGUUUAUUUUAUUUAUUUAUUUAUUUAUUUAUUUAUUUAUUUAUUUUUUGAGAUGGAGUCUCGAUCUGUCACCCAGGCUGGAGUGCAGUGGCGUGACCUCAGCUCACUGCAACCUCCGCCUCCCGGGUUCACACCAUUCUCCUGCCUUAGCCUCCCGAGUAGCUGGGACUACAGGCGUCCGCCACCACACCUGGCUAAUUUUUUGUAUUUUUAGUAGAGACAGGGUUUCACUGUGUUAGCUAGGAUAGUCUUGAUCUCCUCACCUCGUGAUCCGCCCGCCUGGGCCUCCCAAAGUGCUGGGAUUACAGGCCUGAGGAGCCACGCCCGGCCCAUUGCAUGUUUAUGUGUUCCAUGUUAGUCAUUUUAGAAAAUAUUAACAUUAGAACUGCUUUGUAGUUGGGAAAUGGAUGAGACUUAAAAUAGGUUUUAUAAGAUACGAAGUACUUAAAUAUAUUAGACUUGGGGAAGUUAUUCUCUGUGAACUUUGCAAUCUUUAUCUGAAACUGAGCCAGAUGUGAAUCAGAAUUCAGAAAUGUUCUUCGUUCAAAAAAGAAUAUGGUGCAUAUAUUGUAUUACACAAUAACUUCAAAGGGUCCUUGGGUUGCGUCUCAUAAACACAGCAGAAUACAUGAAUAUUCUUACUAAAUGGGAUAAAAGCUAUCAAAUAUUUCAUUCCUUUUUAUUGUUGAAAAAUAUUCAGCCAUAUGGAUUUAUUACAUUUUGCUUAUCCAUUCAAACCAUUGAUGGACAUUUGGCUUGUUCCUAGUUUUAGGCAGUUAUAAAUAGUGUUGCUGUGAACAGUCAUAUACUUUUCUUUUGGCCAACAAGCUUAUAUUCGUUUUGGGUGGAUUGCUAGGAGUUGAAUUGCUGGUUUGAAUAGUAAAUUUAUGUUUAACUUUUUAAGAAACUGACUAUCCAAAGUGACUGUGCCAUUUUACAUUCUCCUUAGCAAUGCAUGAGAGUUACAGUUUCUCUGUAUACUCACCAACACUUGAUAUUGUCUUUUUAAAAUUAUAGCCAUUCUAGUGGAUGUGGUUUCUCAUAGUUAAAUUCGUAUUUCCCUAAUGGCUAAUAAUAUUGAAAAUCUUUUCAUGUGCAUUUUCAGCCAUUUAUCUUCUUUGGUGAACUGUCCAUUUAAAUCUUUUGCCCAUUUUAAAAAACCAGGUUGUCUUUUUAUUAGAGUUGUAGUAGUUCUUUAUGUAUUCUGGAUAUGAGCCCUUUGUUAGAUGUAUCAUUUAUAAACAUUUUUUUCUCAGCCUAUGGCUUGGCUUUUCAUUUUUUAAUGGGGUCUUUUGAAGUGCAGAAAUUUUUUAUUUUGAUGAAUUGAAGUCCAAUUUAUGAACUUUAUAAAAAUAGAUCAUGUUUGGUGUUCGAAGAACUCUUCAAGAAGUUUUAUAGGUUUAGUUCUUCAUUUAAGUAUGGUCCAUUUUGGGUUUUGUGUAUGAUGCAAGGUAAGCAUCUCAUUUCAUUUUUAUGCAUGUAGAUAUUCAGUUGUCUCAGUACCAUUUCCUGCGCUGAGAAUGGAUCACAUGCCCUCUGGUUCAGCCUAUAUUAACAUUUGUUUCUAGGAAAAUGUUUUUAAUUUCUUUUUCAUCAAAAAGUCACUUAUACAAUGAGUAUAAAUGACUAAGGGAAAACCUAUUUCUGUUUAAUUUUAUUUCUAUUCAGAGCAGUUACUAGAGAAUAUAGAAAUUAAAGGAAUCAAUCACCUUUAAAGCUGGGUUUCCUACCAUUGUAUUUCAUGUUCUGAAGUAAGGAUGUAUUGUGUGUGCCAACUGGCCCAUGAUAGACAUACACAGUAGACUGUGGCAGCCUUUCUGGCUUAUCCCCAGCAAGUUGAGAUUGAGGCUCGUGCUAUAAUUAUUUAUGGCAGCUAGACUCUGCUUCUUUGAAUCUAAUUAUGUACAUCCUGGGCUUGUAGGUCUCUGAAGUUACUAGGGGUUAUAUUCUGUAUAAGGGGGUUUACUCUUAAGAAUUUUGGACCUCCCACAUGAUAUUUAGCUAUAUGUUGGGCUAAAGUCUUCACUUCAGAUUUGAGCCAUGUAUUUACCUUCAUUAUGACUGCUUGACUAUGGGAGUCACAAUGUAAAGGUACAGAUCAAACAGACAUACUGUGUUAGUGUUUUUGGAAAGUAAGUUCAAAGCCAGAAAUACUGUGGAGACUAAGCUGAAGUCAGAAUUGUCCUUUUCAGAGUGUUUUAUACGGAGAAACAGUUACAUAGCAUUAUGAGAAUUAAUUCAGUGGAUGAAACCUAAAAACAUUCCCUUUCUAUGUUAUGUACUAGACAUUUAAAAAAAAAAUCUCUGCUCCCAUUAAAGUCAGGUUUCUUAGCAAUUAGGUUAGCAUCAAACAUGCUCGUGUUUUUCCAAGAUUGAAACCCUUUGUGCCAAGGCAUCAAUGUGGUUGCUUCUGUAAGCCUAGUUUAUAGCAAAGAAUAUGCAAGAACAGAGAAAUUAUGGGCCACACCAUGUCAGGCUAGGGAAUAGGGAGGUUUUGGGAUUAUGAUUGGUUCGUGCCAUCAGAAUGCUACAAAGAGAGUAGGCCCUGGAGCCAGAAGUUUUAGAAUUCUCAGAAAGUCUGGAGAUUGUGUUAUAGCAUCCAUAUUGGAGAUUAUUUAGGGAUUCAAAGCUAUCAGAAACUCAGUUUUGUGAAUGGUUAUUUCACAUCCUAGCAUUGAGUAUAUAUGGGAAUGUGAAUCAUGUUAAAUUCAUAAUUGAUUUUCUUUGAAAAUGCUAAACUGCUACUGAAAUAACUACUGCACUGGGCCGUUUGCCAGGGAUGGUAGCCUGAGAUAUGGGGAAACAAGUGUCUCAACCAGAACAAUGUGGAAAUAAGAUUAUUGGAUUUCAUCACAAGUAAGAGAUUCUCCUGAAUUCUCACAAUUUGGGAGAGAGAUGAUAUAAAGGCAACAUACUCAGAAGUAAAAAUGGUGGUGGACCAAUCUCAACCCUGAGAUUCCGAGGUAGACUUAUAUUUAUAUUAUGAAUUUUGUAUUAUGCAUAUGGCACUAUGUAUUAUUUGCGAAUAUGAGAUACAAAAUGUCUUCCCAGUUUGUAGCCUUUUAUUUGAUUUUCUAUGGGGUUUUGUUGAACAGAAGUUUUUAAUUCUAUUGUAUCUGCAGUUAUUAUUAUCUUCCAUUAUGAUGUGUAUUUUCUGUCUUAAGAAAACCUUCUUUGCCCUAAGGUCUUAAGAUGUUCUCCUAUGUUUUCAUCCUAAAGUUUGUUGUUGUUGUUUUAUUUUUUUCUUUGUAACGGAGUUUUGCUCUUGUUGCCCAGGCUGGAGUGCAAUGGCAUGAUCUCGGCUCACCGCAACCUCCGCCUCCCGGGUUCAAGCGAUUCUCCUGCCUCAGCUUCCCGAGUGGCUGGGAUUACAGGCAUGCACCACCACACCCAGCUAGUUUUUGUAUUUUAGUAGAGACGAGGUUUCUCCAUGUUGGUCAGGCUGGUCUUGAACCCCCGACCUCAAGUGAUCCGCCCACCUCAGCCUCCCAAAGUACUAGGGUUACAGGCAUGAGCCACCACACCCAGCCUCAUCCUAAAGUUUUAAAGUAUUGCUUUUCACAUUCAGUUACUUGUCCAUAUAGGAUAUAGUUUUGUUAUAUGCUGGGAAUAGUUAUAAUUUUUCUUUCCUGUUUAAAUGGUUGUUUCAGGUUAUUUAUGGAAUAGUCUGUACUUUCCUCACUGGUUUCUGAUGGGGCUUUUUUAUAUACCAUGCUCUCACAUAUAUGUAAUUCUGUUUUAAAGCUCUUUCAUUUCUGUCAUCUAUGUCUAUAACAAAAUCACACUGUCUUAAUUUCUAUAGCUUUGGGAUAAGUCUUGCUAUCUGAUUAGGGCAGAUAAUCUUCCAAAUUCAAAAACCUGGCUCUUCAAAAUUGAUUUGGCCUUUUGAAUGAUUUUUAGAAUCAACAUGUCAAAUUCUGUAAAUAAUCCUAUGGAGAAUUUCAUUGGCAUUGCUUUGACUUUUUAAAUAUGGCUCAUAUUGUCAUCUUUAACUUGUCUUCCACUAUCUAUGUAUGUGGUAUUUCCAUUUAUGCACCCUUCCUUUUAUUCUUUAAAUAAAGUUUUAUACUUUUUUUUGAAAAGAUCUUAUAAAUACUUUGUUAGAUUCAUUCCUAGGUACUUCACGAGUUUUGUUACUGUGAAUGUUAUCUUUUUAAAAAUUAUAGUUUCUAACUGCUUUUUUAAAAAAAUAGAAUUGCAGUUGAUUUUGUGUAUGGAUCUUAUAUCUAACUACUAUACUGAAUUCUCUUGAAGUUCUUACGUGUGCAUUGUCUGCAAUGGUGACAUUUUUAUUUUAUCUUUCUGGUUCUUACUGCUUUUAUUUCUUUUUCAGAUUGUGCUGAUUAGCCCUACAGUUUUGAAUAGAAGCAGUGAUAGGCAUUUUUGUUUUGUUUUCUGACUUUAAAGGGAAAUGCUUCUAACAUUUCAUACUCCCAGAAUGUAGUUUGCUAUGGGUUUUUCUGGAUACCCUCUAUCACAUUAAAGAGCUUUCCUUCUGUUCCUUGUCGUAAAGAGAUACUGAUUCUUCUUUACCUCAAGUUGCAUUUUGAUUACAAUAUUUCCCCUUCCCCCCGCCCCAUCCAUGAUUUUGUUUUCUGUGGUUUUAGUUACCCUGGUACAAAAGUAUUACAUACAGUAAGGGGGGAGAGAAAGAGACCACAUUCACAUAACUUUCAUUAAUACAGAAUAUUGUUAAUUGUUCUAUUUUAUUAUUUUUGUUAAUCUCUUACUGUGCCUAAUUUACAAAUUAAACUAUCUUAGGUAUAUGUAUAUAUAGGGAUAAAAUAGUAUAUGUAGAGUUCACUACUAUCCAGGGUUUCAGGCAUCCACUGAGUCUUGGAAUUUAUCCCCCAUGAAUAAAUAGGGGACUACUGCAUAUCUUUUUAAUGGUUUUGAGGUAAUCAUAUAAUUUCCCCCCUUAAAAUCUGUUAUUAGAGUGAAUUACAUUAAUAUAUUUUCCUUUUUUUUUUUUUUUUUUUUUAAAGUGAGACAGGGCUCACUGUGUUGGCCAGGCUGGAGUGCAGUGGCAUGAUCAUGGCUCACUGCAACCUUGACCUCCAAGGUUAAGGUGAUCCUCCCACCUCAGCACCCCAGAGUAGCUGGGACUACAGGCACAUGUCACCAUAUCUGGCUAACUUUUUGUAUUUUUAGUAGAGACAGGGUUUUGCCGUGUUGCCCAUGCUGAUCUUGGACUUCUGAGCUUAAGUGAUCCACCCGCCUCAGCCUACCAAAGUGCUGGGAUUACAAGUGUGAGCCACUGUGCUGAGCGAUUUUCCUAACUUUAAAUUAUCCUCACGUUUCUAGGAUAACACCUACUAGGCCCAAAAUACAUUUAAAAUGUAUAUUGCAACCGUUUCUCUUCCCUUCCUGAAUAAUUCAGUCCUGAAGCCAUUAUGUGGGUCAAAGCAAGGUAUGUAUCUGCAAGGGGGGGUGGGGUGCUGCAAUGGCCCAGAGUGGAAUGUCAAAGCCCAGAUUGAGUAGUAGCAUCAUGUUGGGGGAAGGCAUCAGACCCCACUCAAGAUAAGGAGGGCACCAUAGGGAGGUGACUGGGGUGGCUGUGUGUGGGGAUUUAGGGCCCAGGUGAGAUGAGUUAGGCAUCCAUGGGUGGGGAAGGAGCUACCUGGUAUGGGGAGUCAGAGCCAGAGCAGGGUGAGCAGGCAUAGGGGCAGCCUGGCAUAGUAUGUGAGAGCCUAAGCAGAACAGGAAGGGACAACUACCUAGAGAGCCGCCUAGUUCCAGCAUGCCGAGUCAAAGCCUAAGCAGAGUGAGGAGGGCAGACACUACUUUAAUCAAGGGAUCAAAAUGAACAUCAUCCAUAAUGUGUACCACCUGAUAGGAUAUAAUGAGAAGAAAUGACCAUUACUUCUGUGCUGUUCUCACUAAAAAUGCGUAGCCUAAAUCUAAUCAAGAGAAAAUACUAAAGCCAAAUUGAGGGAUAUUCUACAAAAUAGGUGGCCUAUAAUAAUCUCCAAUGGUGCCAGGGUCCUGAAAGAGUCUUUCAAGUGUUACUUAGGAUUUAAGGAGACUGAAGGGACAUGACAAAUGCAAACUGUACUACUACUGUAUCUUUUUCUAUAAAACGUCAUUGGGAUAAUUUGGCAUACGUGAAUAAUGUCUGCAGAUUAAAUAAUAGUAAUGUAUCAGUGUUUAUUGCCUGAUUCUGGUGGUCAUACUGUGGUUAUGUGGGAGAAUGUACUUGUUUGUAGGAAAUACAUACUCUUUGAAGGUAGUGAGGCAUUAGGUUGGCCACUAACUACCAAAUAGCUUAGGAAAAAAAUGUCUUUGUACUGUAUCGCCAACUUUUCUGUAACUUUGUGAUUGUUUCAAAAAUUUUUUUUUAAUUUAAAGUUUAUUGUAGGAUUUGGUUGGUAACAUUUAGGAUUUUUUUUUUUUUUUUUUUUUUUUUUGAUACUAAGUCUCGCUCUUAUCGCCCAGGCUGGAGUGCAAUGGCACGAUCUUGCCUCACUGCAACCUCCGCCUCCUGGGUUCAAGCGAUUCUCCUGCCUCAGCCUCCCGAAUAGCUGGGAUUACAGGCGCCUUCCACCAUGCCCAGCUAAUUUUUGUAUUUUUAGUAGAGACUGGGUUUCACCAUGUUGGCCAGGCUGGUCUCGAACACCUGACCUCAGGCAGUCUCCCUGCCUCAGCCUCGCAAAGUGCUGGGAUUACAGGCGUGAACCACUGCGCCUGGCCACAUUUAGGAUUUUUAAAUCGCUGUGUAUGUCUGAGAUUGGCCUGUGAUUUUUUUCCUUUCUCAUACCGUAUGUACCCAGUUUUAAUCUCAAGUUUAUAGUACCCUCAAACAAUGAAUUAGUGAAUUUUCCCACUCUUCCUUUCAUCCAAAAGCUUCUGUAAUAAAGAGAUUAUCUGUUUCCUAAAGAAUUGUUUGCUGGGGUUUUUUCCCGCUCUCCACUGGCCCCAGACAUGAUAUCUCUCUCUGUCUUCAGGCUGUAGUGCAGUGGCAAGAUCAUAGCUCACUGCAACCUCAAACUCCUGGGCUCGAGCGAUCCUCCAGCUUUAGCCUCCCAAGUAGCUGGGACUACAGACAUGUGCCACUACACCUGGCUAAUUUUUUAAAUUAUUGGUAGAGAUGAGGUCUUGCUAUGUUGCUCUGGCUGGUCUCGAACCCCUGGCCUCAAAUUAUCCUCCCACCUUGGCUUCCCCAAGUGCUGGUAUUACAGACAUAAGCCACCAUGCCCAGCCUGCUUGCUGGACUUUUCUAUAAAAAUUGUAUGAUAAUUAUUUUUUUUUCUUAACCUGGAUUUAGUUUCUUAAUAGGUAAAGGACUAUUUUUUUCUAUUUCUUUGUGAGACCAUUUUAAAAUGUUAGAACAUUUUAGUAAUGUUCUAACCAUUCCCAUUUUAUUCAGAUUUUUAAGUUAUUUUCAGAUAAGAUGAUUCUUAAUAAUCUUAUUUCAAAUAAUAUUAUUCAAUAUAUUUUGAUUUUAAAACAUCUUUAUUGCUCUUGUAGUUAUGGUUCCUUUCUCAUUUCCAAUACUGUUGAUUUGUGCCUUCUCUUUUUUUCUUGACCAGCUUUGCCAGAUGACUAGGUUUAGUUUUGUUGACCCUCUCUGUGUGUUUUCUUAUUUUUUUAAACAUCCUCACCACAAUCUGUGUCUUUAUUUUCUAUGUCAUUUAUUUCUCAUCUCAGUUUUAUUACUUUUACGUUUUUAUACUCUGAGUUUAUCCUGUUCUUUGUCCAAUUUAAGUUGGCUACUUAGUUAUUUUCGCCAAAUUUUGCAUAAUAAACCACUAAAACCUUAGUAGCAUUUAAUGUAAGCAUUAUCGCUCACUCAUCUGAGGUCUGGCUAAGUAUCUGUUGAUCUUGGCUGGACUGAUAGAUAUGUUUCAGAUUGGCUGUUACCUGAUACAGGUUGGACUCAACUGGAGCAACAGGAUGACAUCUACCUCUCAUUACCCUGCUGGGGACAGCAAGCUAAUCUGGACGUAUCUUCUCAUUGUGAGGGCAGAAGCAUAAAAGAAAACAAGAUGCUUAAACUUACAGCUGUCCUACUAUCACUUCUGCCCCAUUCUCUUGGUCAGAACAGGUCACAUGGUUAGGAAAAUAUUUUCUACCAUUAUGAUAAGUACUCCAAAGUCAUGUGACAAAGGACAGGGAAACAAGGAGAGGUGAAGAAUUCAAUCUACCACACUUCCCACCCUCAGUACUUUGCUUUUCAAACUCUUCAUAACAGAAAAGUUAAAAGAAUAGUACCAUGAAUACCCACAUAGCUUUCACCGAGAUUCCCCCUUCAUUCACAUUUUGCCAUAUUUGCUUUAUCUCACAUUUUAUUUUCUGAAUCCUUUAAGAGUUAGCCAGUAUUAUGACAUUGCCCCCCUUAUAUACUUUAAGCGUUUAUCUCCUAAGGCCAAAUACAUUUUUCUGUAUACUCACAACACAAUCAUCACACUCAGGAAAUGUAAUAUUGACACACCACUAUUAUCUAAUUACAAUAUAUAUUUAAAUUUCUCCAUUUGUCCCAAUAAUAUUCUCUUUGGCUAUUCUUUAUUUUCUCUUUUUAAAUGCAGCCAGUUUUGUUUUAUUACAAUAUAUGAAUUCCUAACAAUCACUUUGUCAUGCAAAAUUGCACAUUAAAGAUCACGGGGCUUACCGAAAAAGUGUACUUAGAGACACAGCAUGCAAAAACGUCAUCACACACGCAGAACCUUAUUGAAACAGUAGCACAGUUUUAUACCUAUUAAGUAGUUAAAUACAUAGGUAGUUUACCUUGAAAAAGAUCUGAAGUUUCUUUGCAGAAGUGGGCACCAGAAGGAAAGUGGGUGUCGAAAGGGAUGUAGUUUGUGAGUUAAUGUGAAUUAGCAGGAGGAGAGUUCUCUGAAAUUGGAUAGAAAGUUGUAACACCACUUGUGAAUGGGUAUCGCUAAUAACACUCAUGGUGAACUAAGGUAGCUGGUACAUCUUUGAUUUGCGUGCGCAUGUGCAUUUUGCGUAUUCUAACAGCUCAGUUCAUUUGGGUACAGUUGUCUGCUUUCACCUAAUGUUUCCCACCAAAAAAUAGUACAUAAGCAAAUGAGAAAUUCUUGUUUUGCUAAUGUUGUGUCAGAACAAAUGUGUAUAUAUGUACUUUUUUAAGCUGUAACAGAAGUGACAGUAUAAACAUUUGCAUCUAAAACUGUCCCUCUUAAGAUUGCUUUAGCUGCAUCCUACGAAUUUUGAUAGGUUGUGUUUUUGCUGUAAUUCAAGUCUAAGUAUUCUCUGAUUUCUAUUAUGGUUUCUUUUACCCCUGACUGAGAAGUACAGUUUAAAAUUUCAAGUUUGUAGUUUUCUUUGUUAGGGUAUUCUUUUGUUAAGUGUUUAACUUUAUUGCGUUUUAUUCAAAGAAUGUGGAAAAAUGUGAAAAAAAUAUAAAAAAUGUGAAACAUAUUCUUUAUUUCAUGUGACUGUCUACGUGGCCUAGUUUGUGUUCAGUUUUUGUAACUGUUUUACUUGUGUUUGUGAAGAAUGUGCAUUUUCUAAUUGGUGAGUCCAGUUUCUCCAGACGUAAAUUAUUGUAUUUUUUUCUUAGCUUAAUUUUCUGUGUGUUUAUCACCAAUUCAAUCCAAAUUCUCCCUCAAUUGUUUAAAUCUCCUCUAAGCUUAUUCAAGCACAUUAGGUUAUCUAUCAAUUUCAUCUUGAAGAAAUUUAUCCAAAAUCCAUCUAAUAUGCUAUAAUUAUUUUCCAGGCCCAUUGCACAACUGUCUUCUUGGAAUCUUACUUGCAUUCAUCUCUCUCAUGUUAGAGCUCCCUUUUUUCUGUGUAUCAUUCUGACUCCUUUCCUGGUUUAUUUUUCAUUUUGGUGAAAUUCUUUCUUCAGUAACAUCCUGAAAAAAUGUGCCUAGAAGGUAAAAAAUUUUAGACCACGUAUGUCCGAAAAUGACUUUUCUAUUUUAAUAGUUACAAUCGUUGGAUAUAAAUAGUUUCCCCAUAGCUUUUAAUGCAGUGCUUCAUUUUCUUUUUGCUCCAGUGUUGCAGUUGAGAAGUCUGCUGCCUCUUCCCCCACCAAUCUUAUUUUGAUCCUCUCUUUGUUUUUGAGCUCUAAAAUUUUAUGAGAAAGUACUUUGGUACAGUUCUAUUUUCAGUAAUUGUGCUGGACAUUCAGUGGGUCUUUUCAUUCCUAAAAUUCAUGUUCUUAGGUUCUAGAAAAUUAAUUUGAAUUAAAUAUUUUCUUUAUUCCCCUCAAUUUCUCUAUUCUGACUUCCUGGAACUCCUGUUAUUUAUUAUGGGACCUCUAGCAUUAUUCUUUAAAUUUUAAAAUCUUUUUUCUCCUAUCCAUAAUUUUUAUUAGUCUUUUUUCCCUUAACUAUUUCUUAUAACAUGGUGUUUUUGUUCGUAGAUGUAAUAUGUUUUCUCACAUAUCGAAGAAUAUCAGUGAUAGUUUCUUGAAAUUUUACUUUCUUCCUGCAUGAUUUCUCUUUAUUCAAAGUUGCUUUUUUUUUCCCCCUUGUUUUGAUUUCUCUCAACAUUAGAAGCUUUUUAAAAAUGUCUACUGGUCUUUAAAUACCAUAUUUAAGGGUAUACUGCUAAAAAGGUGAUUGAGAGCUCCAAGUUCAUGUAUGACAUUUGUUGUGAUUUUCACAAAUAAGGGGGUCUAGUUUGUUUCAGUCCCUGAUGAAGGCUUGGUGUCAGAAUAUUGGGUCUUUUCUUUUUGAUUUCCCAGAAAAAGACUCAGCUAGGGACCUGGAAGUUCAGGCAGUGAGUUGGAAAAAAGGGGCUUGCUGUCUAUAGGGAGUAUGUAAAGUUGACUUAUUGCCCUGAAAAGUAAGAUACUUUUCCUUGACUGUGUCCAAACACCUCUUUUUAAACUUCUUUACUGAGGAAGAGUGGCAGUACCUCGCUUGGGUUUUCUAGGUGUGGAGAGUGAGGAGGAAAUCAGGGAGGCUUAACUCCUAAAAUAGACUUUUCAACCAGUUAUCUCAUUUUUAGCCCCACUUUCACCCCCCCCUCCCCAUUUUCAGAGGCAUCUAGUGCUCCCAGUUCCUGAGCCCUUUGGUGAUUAUGCAGAGUUAGUGGGUUUUGUUUGUUUGUUUGUUCUUGUUGUUGUUUUUACCUAAAGCCUAUUUAGGAGUCACUUUUCUUGGAGUGUCAGUCUUACAUAUGCUUUCCAGCUUUUAAGAUUUUAUUUCUUUUUGUUCCAUUCCCAUGUUCCUAUUCUUAUGGAUUUAUGCCACUUUAAAAAAAAUUACUGUAGUUUCAGUGAGGUUUGGGGAGAGGAGAGUAAGGUGCAAAGUGAAUGUGUCCAGUCUACCAUUUCUACACAAAACCUUAAAAUACAUUUUAAUAACUUAGAAGUUUUAAAGAGUAUUUCACAUUCAUCAAAGGCUCCUCAGCGGGUUUAGAAGGUCAAAACUGUAAGACAUUAUUUGCCACCUUUCAGUCGUGUACAGUGGAGUUUUCCAAAGUUUACAUGAUGUGUGGUAUUGCAGCAAAUUAAGUGCAUAAACUGAUAGGAGAAACCUGCUCUUUUCUCUUGUCAGGCAUUGAAGAGAUUUGAAAAAUGUAAAACAAUGCCUCUCUUUUCACUUUUUUCAGAAAAUGCAUUUUUAUUAAAAAUAUCUUAUUUAUGGUAAUGUGAUGGGUUUAUUGUUAUUUUAAACUUGUUUAUAAGUAAGUAAAAGUCUCAGUUUUUGUUUUGAAUAUGGUGAAUGUCAGUAGUUGUAACUCACAUAAACAACUCUUUGGGAUCCUCAGUAAUUUUUAAGAGAGUAAAGAGUCAUGAGAUCAAAAUGUUUGAGAACUUCUGUUCUAGAGAACCCUAGAUGUAAAUUGGAAGUGGAACAUGAAUGUAAUAAUAUAACCAUAACCAACACUCCACUAGUCUUAUCUUUACAUAGGACAAUAAUGUAAUUUAAUCCCCAUGUUUAUUAAAUGUAACACCCCCGCGGUUUUAUUUCUCUUUUAUUUUCCCUCGUGGUAAUCCUUAGGGCAACUAAAGGAAGCUAUCAGAAGUUAAUCUAUACUCUUUCUCCCUAAAGCAUGUAUGUUCUAGACUCUGCUUAUUUAAAUAAUGAGAAAUAAACUUAAGAGCCAAAUUGUUAAAGUGUGCAUUUUUGUUCUCAAGGGGUUAAAAAUUGGCUCUUAAAGAAAAAAAUUUUUUUUUAAAUUGUUUGUUACAUGUAAACAGAUACAUAGUUUAAUUUGUGGUAUCAAAAUAUCAUUGAGGAUGAUGAACAAUUAGGAAAAAAAGUCAAAAGUCUCCUUAAGAGGGGACAAUAAUGAAAAACACCGCAAGAAACAGUGUGUUAGAGAUCCUUUAACCUCUUACCUAUUUCUUCUAUCCUAGGCUUGCCCCAGAACACACACUAUAGAGCAGAUGCAGUAGCCACAAAUAACUUUGUGGGGAUCUAGUAGCUCCCUUAAAGAAUGAGGUGAGGCAGGCUGAAGCGGGCGGAUCACGAGGUCAAGAGAUCAAGACCAUCCUGGCUGACAAGAAAGGCAAUUUUUACUUUCUGCGGAAAGGGUGCUCCUUGCAGAUGGAACAAUGGUGAGACCACACCCGGACAGGGGAGGGGAAGGAGUUCUUGUUCCUGACGCAGGUAUCCCCUACUGCUGUGUCAUUCCUGUAUUGGCUAGGGUUGGCCCGCACAGUCUAAGCUAAUUCCAACUGGCUAUUUUAAAAAGAGCAGGGGGUAUGAGCCAGAGUGGUAGGGUGAGUAGUUUGGCGGGAAGGAUGGUUAGAAACAGGUAACUAAAGGUGACUUAGGUCAGAGCAGGUGACCAGGGGUGACUCAGGUAAAGCAGGUGACCGGGAUGAGUCAGGAUGGACCAGGUGACCAGGGAACAGAUGUGAACUACUGAUUAGGACUGGUGGGAAAGUUGUUUACUGAAACUUAGAAGCAAGGGGGUGAAGAGAACCAGGAAGCUAAACUUUAAAAUGGAGAAUCAAAGAAUAAGAGAGCUGAACAUACUGACAUACUGAUUCUUUGAAGAGAAACUUGGGGUUCACUAUAUUUAACAGGAUCAAAGGUAAUUUUCUUCUUCUUUGGUGGGCCUGGACUUUAGACAGAUAAGGAAACUUCACAGAACAACUUCAUACUGUGUUUUGCGAGAAAGAGGAUCAAGAGAUGGGAAGAAACAGGGGAAGGUCGGAGAGACUCUGAGGCUGCUUCUUCAGCAUGUCAAAGUGCCACAGUUUGGGGUAUCAGUUUCUGAGCCCCAGCACCUGCAAAAGAAAAGAAACCUGAAUUUCCAUAUGUUUGAUUAAAUGAGUCUUAAACCCUGAAGUGUGGAGAGGACCAAUUGUGGCAGUCUUCUGUGUUAUAAAAACAUUUAAUUAGAAUCUCUCUUCAUUUAGCAUAACUAUAGAACCUUUUAGACACUCCUAGAAUAUGCAGAGAAAUGGAAAACUUCAGAAGAUCCUUUACCUUUAUUGGAGGUAUACACAGUGGCUAUCCAAAGUUAUGUUAAAGCCCGACCUUAUCUUACCUCUGAAUGUGAAAAUGUAGCCUUGGUUCUGGAACGCUUGGCAUUAAGCUGUGUUGAACUUUUACUGUGUCUGCCUGUUGAGUUAUCAGAUAAACAGUGGGAACAAUUUCAGACACUGGUGCAGGUAGCUCAUGAAAAGCUGAUGGAGAAUGGCAGCUGUGAAUUGCAUUUUUUAGCUACUCUAGCUCAAGAGACUGGGGUGUGGAAAAACCCGGUACUGUGCACUAUUCUUUCCCAGGAACCAUUGGAUAAGGAUAAAGUGAAUGAAUUUUUAGCUUUUGAGGGUCCCAUCUUGUUGGAUAUGAGAAUUAAACAUCUAAUCAAAACAAAUCAGUUAAGUCAAGCAACUGCUCUAGCAAAGCUGUGUUCUGACCAUCCAGAGAUUGGCAUAAAAGGUAGUUUUAAGCAAACUUACCUUGUCUGUCUUUGUACAUCAUCACCAAAUGGAAAGUUAAUCGAAGAGAUUUCAGAAGUUGAUUGCAAAGAUGCACUGGAAAUGAUCUGUAACUUAGAAUCUGAGGGUGAUGAAAAAAGCGCUCUUGUUUUAUGUACUGCGUUUUUGUCACGUCAGCUCCAACAAGGAGAUAUGUACUGCGCUUGGGAACUUACUCUCUUUUGGAGUAAAUUACAACAAAGAGUAGAACCAUCUAUACAAGUGUACCUUGAGAGGUGUCGUCAACUUUCUUUGUUAACGAAAACAGUAUAUCACAUUUUCUUCCUGAUUAAAGUUAUUAAUUCAGAGACUGAAGGGGCUGGACUUGCUACCUGUAUAGAACUGUGUGUAAAGGCUCUUCGCUUGGAGUCUACAGAAAAUACUGAAGUGAAAAUAUCUAUUUGCAAGACCAUUUCAUGUUUGUUGCCUGAUGAUCUGGAAGUUAAACGUGCUUGUCAACUGAGUGAAUUUCUUAUUGAGCCUACAGUAGAUGCGUAUUAUGCUGUGGAAAUGUUGUAUAAUCAGCCAGACCAGAAAUAUGAUGAAGAGAAUCUUCCAAUACCAAAUUCUUUACGCUGUGAGCUGUUACUUGUAUUGAAAACUCAAUGGCCCUUUGAUCCAGAAUUCUGGGAUUGGAAAACCUUGAAACGACAAUGUCUUGCAUUAAUGGGAGAAGAAGCAUCCAUUGUGUCUUCAAUAGAUGAACUAAAUGACAGUGAAGUAUAUGAAAAAGUGGUAGACUACCAAGAAGAGAGUAAAGAAACUUCUAUGAAUGGGCUUUCUGGUGGAGUUGGUGCUAAUUCUGGCCUUCUUAAAGACAUUGGUGAUGAAAAGCAGAAGAAGAGAGAGAUAAAACAGUUAAGAGAGAGGGGAUUUAUAUCUGCUCGGUUUAGGAAUUGGCAAGCCUACAUGCAGUAUUGUGUGUUGUGUGACAAAGAAUUCCUUGGUCACAGAAUAGUACGACAUGCUCAGAAACAUUACAAAGAUGGAAUUUAUAGUUGCCCCAUAUGUGCAAAGAACUUUAAUUCUAAAGAAACUUUUGUCCCUCAUGUCACACUGCAUGUUAAACAAUCUAGUAAAGAGAGACUAGCAGCUAUGAAACCAUUAAGAAGAUUGGGAAGGCCUCCAAAGAUCACAACUACCAAUGAAAAUCAGAAGACUAAUACUGUGGCUAAACAGGAGCAGCGACCUAUAAAAAAGAAUAGUCUCUAUUCAACAGAUUUUAUAGUGUUUAAUGACAAUGAUGGUUCAGAUGAUGAGAAUGAUGACAAAGAUAAAUCCUAUGAGCCAGAAGUGAUUCCAGUCCAGAAACCAGUACCUGUUAAUGAAUUUAAUUGCCCUGUAACUUUUUGUAAAAAGGGCUUUAAGUACUUUAAAAAUUUAAUUGCUCAUGUGAAGGGGCAUAAAGAUAAUGAAGACGCCAAGCGCUUUCUUGAAAUGCAGAGCAAAAAAGUUAUUUGCCAGUACUGUAGGCGGCAUUUUGUGAGUGUUACUCAUCUCAAUGAUCACUUACAGAUGCACUGUGGCAGUAAACCAUAUAUCUGUAUACAGAUGAAAUGUAAAGCUGGUUUUAAUAGUUACGCCGAGCUUUUAACCCACCGAAAGGAGCAUCAAGUCUUUAGAGCAAAAUGUAUGUUUCCUAAAUGUGGAAGAAUUUUUUCGGAAGCUUAUUUACUAUAUGAUCAUGAAGCACAACAUUAUAAUACGUACACUUGUAAGUUCACAGGUUGUGGUAAAGUUUAUCGUUCUCAGGGUGAGCUGGAAAAGCAUCUGGAUGAUCACAGUACUCCUCCUGAAAAAGUGCUGCCUCCUGAAGCCCAACUUAAUUCAUCUGGAGAUUCCAUUCAGCCUUCUGAAGUGAAUCAGAACACAGCAGAGAAUAUUGAGAAAGAAAGAUCUAUGCUUCCUUCAGAAAAUAACAUUGAAAACAGCUUACUAGCAGAUAGAAGUGAUGCUUGGGAUAAAAGCAAAGCAGAAUCAGCUGUGACCAAACAAGACCAGAUUUCUGCCUCUGAGCUCAGGCAAGCUAAUGGACCAUUGUCAAAUGGUUUGGAAAACCCUGCUACUACUCCUCUACUUCAAUCCAGUGAAGUAGCUGUGUCCAUUAAGGUGUCUCUCAAUCAGGGGAUUGAGGAUAACUUUGGAAAGCAAGAAAACUCAACUGUGGAAGGCAGUGGUGAAGCACUGGUCACAGACUUACAUACGCCAGUUGAAGAUACUUGUAAUGAUUUGUGUCAUCCAGGUUUCCAGGAGAGAAAAGAACAAGAUUGCUUUAAUGAUGCCCAUGUUACUCAGAAUUCUUUAGUAAAUUCAGAAACUCUCAAAAUAGGUGACCUUACCCCACAAAACUUAGAAAGACAAGUGAACAACUUGAUGACCUUUUCUGUGCAAAAUCAGGCAGCAUUUCAAAACAAUUUACCAACUUCCAAAUUUGAAUGUGGAGAUAAUGUUAAAACAUCAUCCAAUCUUUAUAAUUUACCUCUUAAGACAUUAGAAAGUAUUGCAUUUGUUCCACCGCAGUCCGACCUAAGUAAUUCAUUAGGAACUCCAUCAGUGCCUCCAAAAGCUCCAGUUCAGAAAUUCAGCUGCCAGGUCGAGGGAUGUACUCGAACCUAUAAUUCUUCACAGAGUAUUGGGAAACACAUGAAGACAGCACACCCUGACCAAUAUGCUGCAUUUAAAAUGCAGCGCAAAAGUAAAAAAGGUCAGAAAGCUAACAACUUAAAUACACCAAAUAAUGGAAAGUUUGUUUAUUUUUUGCCAUCACCGGUGAACAGCUCAAAUCCAUUUUUUACAUCACAGACCAAAGCCAAUGGGAAUCCUGCUUGUUCGGCCCAGUUGCAGCAUGUCUCGCCACCCAUUUUUCCAGCUCAUUUAGCAAGUGUGUCAACUCCAUUGUUGUCCUCAAUGGAAAGUGUCAUAAAUCCAAAUAUAACUUCUCAGGAUAAAAAUGAACAAGGUGGUAUGUUAUGUUCCCAAAUGGAAAAUUUACCUAGUACUGCCUUGCCAGCACAAAUGGAAGAUCUAACCAAAACAGUUCUGCCUUUGAAUAUUGACAGUGGCUCAGAUCCUUUCCUUCCUUUACCUGCAGAAAGUAGUUCAAUGUCUCUCUUCCCUUCACCAGCAGAUAGUGGGACUAAUUCUGUUUUUUCCCAACUGGAAAAUAAUACAAAUCAUUAUUCCUCACAGAUUGAAGGAAACACUAAUUCCUCCUUUCUAAAGGGGGGUAAUGGUGAAAAUGCAGUUUUUCCUUCACAAGUGAAUGUUGCAAAUAACUUCAGUAGCACCAAUGCCCAACAGUCUGCACCUGAAAAAGUUAAAAAAGACCGUGGGCGGGGCCCAAAUGGGAAGGAAAGAAAACCUAAGCACAACAAAAGGGCUAAAUGGCCUGCAAUUAUCAGAGAUGGGAAAUUUAUCUGUAGCAGGUGUUACAGGGCUUUUACUAAUCCCAGAUCACUGGGUGGGCACUUAUCCAAGCGAUCUUACUGUAAACCACUGGAUGGAGCCGAAAUUGCUCAAGAACUUCUACAGAGUAAUGGACAGCCUUCUCUUCUUGCCAGCAUGAUUCUCUCCACAAAUGCAGUAAAUUUGCAGCAGCCACAACAAUCUACCUUCAAUCCAGAAGCAUGUUUUAAAGAUCCAUCAUUUCUACAGCUUCUUGCUGAAAAUCGCUCGCCAGCAUUUUUACCAAAUACAUUUCCUCGAUCUGGUGUGACUAACUUUAAUACCAGUGUCAGUCAAGAAGGUAGUGAAAUUAUUAAACAGGCUUUGGAAACUGCUGGCAUUCCCAGUACAUUUGAGGGUGCCGAAAUGCUUUCUCAUGUUUCAACAGGUUGUGUCUCUGAUGCAUCACAAGUAAAUGCAACGGUGAUGCCAAAUCCAACUGUACCACCCCUGUUGCACACUGUAUGCCAUCCAAACACCUUGCUGACCAACCAGAAUAGGACGUCAAACUCCAAAACUUCCUCCAUUGAGGAAUGUAGCAGCUUGCCUGUUUUUCCAACGAAUGACUUACUACUGAAGACUGUUGAAAAUGGUUUGUGCUCUAGUUCAUUUCCUAAUUCUGGUGGGCCAUCACAAAAUUUUACCAGUAACAGUUCUCGUGUUUCUGUUAUAAGUGGUCCUCAGAACACAAGAUCCAGUCAUUUAAAUAAAAAGGGAAACAGUGCUUCUAAGAGAAGAAAGAAAGUUGCUCCUCCACUAAUUGCACCUAACGCUUCCCAAAACUUGGUAACAAGUGACUUAACAACAAUGGGACUCAUAGCAAAGAGUGUUGAAAUCCCAACUACUAACCUUCAUUCAAAUGUAAUUCCAACUUGUGAACCUCAGAGUUUGGUGGAAAAUCUAACACAGAAAUUAAAUAAUGUUAACAAUCAGUUAUUUAUGACUGAUGUAAAAGAGAAUUUCAAAACCAGUCUUGAGUCCCAUACAGUGUUAGCCCCUUUAACAUUAAAAACUGAAAAUGGUGAUUCCCAAAUGAUGGCUUUGAAUUCAUGCACAACUUCAAUAAAUUCUGAUUUGCAGAUUUCUGAAGACAAUGUUAUACAAAACUUUGAAAAGACUCUUGAAAUUAUUAAAACUGCUAUGAAUUCUCAAAUACUUGAGGUAAAAAGUGGAUCUCAGGGUGCUGGUGAAACUUCACAAAAUGCUCAAAUAAAUUAUAACAUUCAGCUUCCUUCAGUAAACACUGUGCAAAAUAACAAAUUACCCGAUUCUUCUCCGUUUUCCUCCUUUAUAAGUGUCAUGCCAACAAAAAGUAACAUUCCUCAGUCUGAAGUAUCACAUAAGGAGGAUCAAAUACAGGAAAUUUUAGAAGGCUUACAGAAAUUAAAAUUAGAAAAUGACCUAUCCACUCCAGCAUCCCAAUGUGUACUGAUAAAUACAUCAGUGACACUGACUCCCACGCCUGUUAAAUCAACUGCAGAUAUCACAGUUAUUCAGCCAGUUUCUGAAAUGAUAAACAUUCAAUUUAAUGACAAAGUUAAUAAACCCUUUGUGUGUCAAAACCAAGGCUGUAACUACAGUGCUAUGACAAAGGAUGCACUAUUUAAGCACUAUGGUAAAAUUCAUCAAUACACUCCAGAAAUGAUUCUUGAAAUUAAGAAGAAUCAAUUGAAAUUUGCUCCCUUUAAAUGUGUAGUACCUACAUGUACAAAAACAUUUACAAGAAAUUCUAACCUCCGGGCACACUGUCAGUUGGUGCAUCAUUUUACAACUGAAGAAAUGGUAAAGUUAAAAAUUAAAAGGCCUUAUGGAAGAAAAUCUCAGAGUGAAAAUGUGCCGGCCUCACGAAGUACACAAGUGAAAAAACAGCUAGCUAUGACAGAGGAAAAUAAAAAGGAAUCUCAGCCUGCUUUAGAAUUGAGAGCAGAGACCCAAAAUACCCACAGUAAUGUAGCAGUGAUCCCAGAAAAACAACUUGUAGAAAAAAAAAGUCCUGACAAAACAGAAAGUUCUUUACAAGUGAUUACAGUUACUUCAGAACAAUGUAAUACAAAUGCACUCACAAACACACAAACCAAAGGACGGAAGAUUAGGAGGCAUAAAAAAGAAAAGGAGGAGAAAAAACGAAAGAAGCCAGUUUCCCAAUCCCUUGAGUUUCCAACAAGAUACAGUCCUUACAGACCUUAUCGAUGUGUUCACCAGGGAUGCUUUGCUGCCUUUACGAUACAGCAAAACUUGAUUCUCCAUUACCAGGCUGUACACAAAUCAGAUCUACCUGCAUUUUCAGCAGAGGUCGAAGAGGAAAGUGAAGCUGGUAAAGAAAGUGAAGAAACUGAAACUAAACAAACUUUGAAAGAAUUUCGAUGUCAGGUAAGUGACUGUUCUCGAAUUUUCCAAGCAAUUACUGGCCUAAUACAACACUACAUGAAACUUCAUGAAAUGACUCCUGAAGAAAUUGAAAGUAUGACUGCUUCAGUGGAUGUUGGGAAGUUUCCAUGUGACCAGUUAGAGUGUAAAUCUUCAUUUACUACAUAUUUGAACUAUGUUGUUCAUCUAGAGGCAGACCACGGGAUUGGACUAAGGGCAAGUAAAACAGAAGAAGAUGGUGUAUACAAAUGUGAUUGUGAAGGCUGUGACCGUAUAUAUGCAACCCGGUCGAAUCUCCUCCGACACAUUUUUAAUAAGCAUAAUGACAAACAUAAGGCUCAUUUGAUUCGUCCAAGAAGAUUAACACCAGGCCAGGAAAAUAUGUCAAGCAAGGCAAACCAAGAAAAAUCAAAGUCUAAACAUCGGGGGACCAAGCACAGCAGAUGUGGAAAGGAAGGAAUAAAAAUGCCCAAGACCAAACGAAAGAAAAAAAAUAAUUUAGAAAACAAGAAUGCAAAGAUUGUGCAGAUUGAAGAAAAUAAGCCUUAUUCUCUGAAACGUGGGAAGCAUGUAUAUUCUAUAAAGGCUAGAAAUGAUGCCCUGUCUGAGUGUACAAGCAGAUUUGUAACCCAGUAUCCAUGUAUGAUAAAGGGAUGUACUUCAGUUGUUACAAGUGAAAGCAAUAUAAUUAGACAUUAUAAGUGCCAUAAAUUAUCUAAGGCAUUUACAUCACAACACCGAAAUCUUCUUAUUGUAUUCAAACGGUGUUGCAACUCACAAGUAAAGGAAACGUCUGAGCAAGAAGGUGCUAAGAAUGAUGUGAAAGAUUCUGACACGUGUGUAUCAGAGAGCAAUGAUAAUUCAAGAACAACAGCUACAGUUUCACAAAAGGAAGUUGAAAAAAAUGAAAAAGAUGAAAUGGAUGAACUAACAGAAUUGUUUAUUACAAAAUUAAUAAAUGAAGAUAGCACAAGUGUAGAGACCCAAGCUAAUACUUCUUCAAAUGUAAGUAAUGAUUUUCAGGAAGAUAACCUCUGCCAGUCAGAAAGACAAAAAGCAAGUAAUUUGAAGAGAGUUAAUAAGGAAAAAAAUGUCUCACAAAAUAAAAAAAGGAAAGUUGAAAAAGCUGAACCAGCAUCAGCAGCUGAGUUAAGUAGCGUGCGUAAAGAAGAAGAAACUGCUGUUGCCAUUCAAACCAUUGAGGAGCAUCCUGCAUCUUUUGACUGGAGCUCUUUUAAGCCAAUGGGAUUUGAAGUAUCAUUUCUGAAGUUUCUUGAGGAGUCUGCAGUGAAGCAGAAGAAAAAUACUGACAAAGACCAUCCGAAUACUGGAAACAAAAAAGGAUCCCAUUCAAAUUCAAGAAAAAAUAUUGAUAAGACUGCUGUGACUAGUGGAAAUCAUGUAUGUCCUUGUAAAGAAAGCGAAACGUUUGUACAGUUUGCCAAUCCAUCACAGCUUCAGUGCAGUGAUAAUGUAAAAAUUGUUUUAGACAAGAAUCUUAAAGAUUGCACUGAGCUUGUCUUAAAGCAACUUCAGGAAAUGAAACCUACCGUCAGUCUGAAAAAACUUGAAGUACAUUCAAAUGAUCCAGAUAUGUCUGUUAUGAAAGAUAUCAGUAUAGGUAAAGCCACAGGCAGAGGUCAGUACUGAUAAUUAAUGUAGUAUAAAUACAUCAUUUACCAUUUUAUUUUAAAUAGGAAGCCAUCAAGCAUGCUAGAAUUGUGAAACUUUCAUUAUAUUUUUUUGUUGUUGACAUGAAUUAACCUGGCCAAAAACAAAAAAGAAAAAAAAAACAUGACAUUUGUCAUGUAAAACUUUUUUUUAUCCCUAUGGGACUUGAGGAACAGAAUCAGUACUUCAGUUAUUGUAAAUAGUGAGCUAAACCUCAAAUUUCUAUCACCCAGUUGCCCUUUUCAUGAACUAAACAAUUAUCUGUGUGAUUGGUAUGUUUCACCAGGUCACUGCUCAUGUAUAACAGUACUCUUUAUUUGUAGAUACCUUUUUUGUAUAUAUUUAUUAUUGUAAAUCAUGUGCUGCCACCAGCAGUCUGUAAGUCUAAACUAUUAAAUGACACAUUUAUAUUUGGAAUUUUAAUUUUUAACUAAGCGAUCAAGUUUUUUAAAUUGUUCUUUUAUUGUUUUAAAUUAAGAACUUUUUGAACUAAAACCAGAAACUCUGCCAUAGUUCAUUGAUUUUUACAUGAAACAUUUAUUUACAAGAUGAUAUCAAGAUUACUUUUCACAAAAUAGGCACAUUAUAUCAACACUUUGCUCUGCUUUGUAAAUUUGCCAUCCAGGAUUUUGGGGUGGUAUUCAUGUGAAAUUAAAGCAGAUUCUCUAGCAGUUUCCUAUAGCUACAGUUUUUUUUUUUCAUUGCUUCUAAUUGGAUAUAGUUACUAUGAGUCCAUGAAAUACAAUGGAAAUGUGAAUAAAGAAUUUACUACAUUGAAGAUUUUAAACAUUUGGUAUUAAAAAAAAAUCCUUUGUGAAUGUGAUAGAAAACUAGUAGUGUGGAGCAGUGUAAAUAUUUGAGGUGGUGAUUUGUGAAGUAGCCCAGUAUUGCCUUAAAUAAAAUCACAUUUCAUUUCUUGUUUUAUACAUGUGAUCUUAUAAAGAUUUUUUGUUUUGUUUUGUUUUCCAUUUUCUGAGAUUUAUAGAUUGGUGUAUAGCUUUAAACUGUAUAAAGUUUUGUGGAAAGAUUUUUUUAAACAUUUUUAUAAAUCUUAAAAUUGAUAUCAUCAAAGUGAGCCCAUCUUGUGUUUAUAAAAUACAAGAGUCCUUAACAUUUAUAAUUACAUAGAUAAAACACUUUCUAUAAGGAAGUUGGAUGUUUUGAUUUUACUGUUUAUAGAUGUUAGAUUGUACAGAUUUGUCUGUAUUUCUCACCAUAUCUAAUGAUACUUUUUUCAUUAGAUUGGUCUUCAAGAACAGUAUUAGUUAUAAUUAUUUUGGUUAUUCAGUAUAUAGUUAGCUCUUACAGUUUAGCUUUAUUCACCAUAUUUAUACUGUGGAUUCACAGCGAGAGGUAGAGGUUAUUCCAGGAGAGUUGAUGACCUUCAUUUAAAGUCCAACUAAAAUCAGUAGUAGAAACAUAAGAAAACAUCUUUGCAAUAUUUACUUUUGUUUCUGUUUGCCGUAAAUAGUAACAUUGUUUUUUUUUAUUUUGUGUUUGUUAUAAAACAGUUGCAUUCACAAUAUUAUUGGCCUGAGAUAUUGAUGAUAUUGUGAUGGUAUGAAAAUGUGUACAUUCCCUGUGCAACAUCAGAUUUGCAGGAAAAAUGAAGCACUUACUGAAAUCGCUGGUACUCUGAAUAAAUAAGCAUGGUCAAGGAGUGAACUAUUUUCUUUUGGAAAUUUCUUUUUAAUUUUUAUUAUUAAAGUAUUUUAUUUUUAGGGCCUUUUGGGUUUUAUUGAAUAGUUCAUUUCACCUGUUUAAGACUUACUACCAAUAAGCAUAAAACCUGACACGUUAAAAUCCCUGCCCUUUGGUGAGCCCACUGUUAUUUAUUAAAAUAAAAGUUAUUUUAUGGGUGAUUAAUACAUGGGUUUUCUUUUUCCUAAAUUAACAAUAAUUUAAAUAACUGAGUAAUUUUAAUAUUAAAUUUUUGUUAACAACUGAAUGUUUCCAUACAGUUUUCUUAGAAAUUGACCUAGCUCUUAAAGGUGGGCACUUGGCAAAACUGCCCUAUAUAGCACAGUAGCAAGUAGGUUUAUUUCUGAUCAUUGUAACUAUGAGCCACUGUUAAGUGAAAAUGCCAAUGUAUUGGGGCUUUUCUUUUGCUCAUUAGCUUAAGAAAAUUUAUAACUAGACAUUUCUAAUUGUUUUACAUGUCAUGGGGAAGAGUUUGCCAACAUUUAAUGAAAUUUUUAUAUUCCAGGUAAUGUAUACUAAAGGUAAUUAUGAGAGUGGGCUUUUUAGCAUGAAACAAAAAAAAUCAAACUAUGGUAAAAAGACAUGAAUUUAUAGAAUAGCAUGUUGGUAAAUUUUGAUACGGAAUGUAAUGUCUAAGUAUUAAAAAAUCAUAAAAUAUAUUUUUUUCAUGGUAUACUUUUCCCCAGCCUAUUGUCUUGAGAUAUCUUCUACAGCCUAAAUUUGCUAAAGUUUCAUCACUAAAAAGUAGGAGUUUUUCCUCUUCUGAACCCGCAAAGUUUGCAUAUUACAGGUCAGAAUUGUAUUAUUCAAAAUACAUCACCUUAAGUGAAAUGUAACAGUUUUUGAAAUUUUCAACGGUGUUAAAUUUAACAUAGGUACAUUAUUAUUUUAAAGGGCUAGACAUAUUUUUAAGGCAAAUUUUUAUCAAGUGAGCAGUCACAGUUGCUGUAGAUAAUAUGAAAGUACAAUAAUACUAUACCUAGGGACAUCAGAAAGAAUGCCCUAUUUUUCUGGAAAAGGAGGUAGGUAGUUGGGAAAGUCUUUGUAGAAAAUAUGAGUUUUGAAAGAUGAAUGAAUGCUCAUUGGUUCAGGGGGACAAGGGAAUUCCAGACUUGGGGGUAGAGCGUAAUUGCGGUAUUGCCAGUGGGCCACUUGGAAAGAUAGGAAGUUGAAGAAGGUGAAGCUGAAGAAGCAGAUGGGUGGUGGGAUCAGGAGUGUUCUUGUAUGCUGUAUUAAGUCUUUAUUUUGGUUUUUGAAAAUUGUUAUUGGAUGCAUGUAUAUUGAACAAUUUAAUCAGUAUCAGUUUUAGAAAGAUAAUUGUCAUGGUAUAGUGGAUAAAUUGAGUAAGUUGGAGAUUAAUUAGGGGGACCUAAAAUAGUCCAGGCAAAAAAUGAUGGGAGCCAGAAGAAAGGCUAACGAAGUUGGGGAAGAGACUAAUGGAUAAGAGAGAUAAUAAAAAGUAAUGUCUAAGGCAGCCUGUUUCAGCAUGUUUAUUGUAGUGAGAUACUAGGCAGGUGGAAGGUUAUUGCUGUGAUGAAAUAAGUUUUCUAAAUUGUGUGCUGUAGUUCUCUCUCUCUCUCUCUCUUUUUUUUUCUUUGUUUUUUUUGGAGACAGAGUCUCGCUCUGUUGCCCAGGCUGGAGUGCAGUGUUGCACGAUCUCGGCUUACUGCAACUUCUGCCUCCCAAGUUCAAGUGAUUCUCCUGCCUCAGCCUCCCCAGUAGCUGGGACUACAGAUGCAUGCUAUCACACCCAGCUAAUUUUGUAGUUUUGGCACAAUCUCAGCUCAGUGCAACUUCCAUCUCCCAGGUUCAAGUGAUUCUCCUACCUCAGCCACCCAAGUAGGUGCACACCACCACACCUGGCUGAUUUUAUAUUUUUAGUAGAGACGGUUUCACCAUGUUGGCCAGGCUGGUCUUGAACUCCUGACCUCAGGUGAUCACCCACCUCCACCUCCCAAAGUGCAGGUAUUACAAGCAUGAGCCACCACACCCAGCCUCUCUUAAAUAAUUUAAUGCAUGUUUGCAUAUUAAAGACAAAAGUUCUACUGUAAAUAUGUAAAAAGUUGAAAGGGAAUUUUCCAGACUUAAUUGACCCUGAGAACAUUUUUCUUCUUUUAAUGUUAAUACUUAGUUAUAUCCCACUGAACUAGCAUUCUAAAGAACACACUUUGGGAAAUGCUGAUCUCAAAUGGCAUUUAUUCAACCAGGACUGAUAAUCAACGUGUACACCAAUUCAAUUGUAUCAGCUGUUUGCAAAUGGUGAUUAUUCUGAUUGAUCAAUUUAUAUAUCCCAAUGGGUUGAUUCCUUUGCUGUAUUGGUUGUUAAUGUUUUGAAUAUUACCCGGUAUUCAAGUAAUGCUCAUUGAAUUUCAAGUAAUUGUGAUUAAACGUUGAUUAAAAUCCAGUCAUACUUGCCAGAA